GAUGAGAGGAACUAGAAGCAGCUAUUGCAAGCUACCAUUUUGAGAACCUGCCCAAAGAAAGAAAAGACUGAAGGGAUGGAAGAUUGCAGAAAGCAUGAUCGGAGAAGAGAUAUUUUACUUUUAGUGAAGCUCUAUACACAUUUGUCUUCCUCACUAGAUUUGUAUCCCUAGAACCUAGAACAGAGUCAGCCAAAGAGCAGGCACUCAAUACAAAUUGUUGACUUGCUGCUAAAAUUGUAACAGAGUACAAAGAACAUCCUAGAAAUUGGAGACAAAGGGGAUAAGAAAACAGAGUUAACUUGGAAAGAGAAGACACUCAUCUCUGACAAGACUGAAGAUGAUUACACAACACCAUCAUUGCCAACCAAGUCCUUUGGGAAUACAAAGGUUAAAUCCUAAUCAUCACAACAGUCUCUAAAGGAAUAAACCUGAUUUACAGAUUUUGAUAACAAAAUACUUCUCCUCUUUCCAUUUUCUACAAUGCAACCAACAGCAACAUCAAAGAGGUUUUUAACUGAAGACUCUAUGCUCUGUAGUUCUUUCCACAAAGAGCUGACUGAUAUUUGAAGAAGUGUUUUCAUCUAUCCAAGAAAAAUAUGAUGUCUCCAUCCCAAGCCUCACUCUUAUUCUUAAAUGUAUGUAUUUUUAUUUGUGGAGAAGCUGUACAAGGUAACUGUGUACAUCAUUCUACGGACUCUUCAGUAGUUAACAUUGUAGAAGAUGGAUCUAAUGCAAAAGAUGAAAGUAAAAGUAAUGAUACUGUUUGUAAGGAAGACUGUGAGGAAUCAUGUGAUGUUAAAACUAAAAUUACACGAGAAGAAAAACAUUUCAUGUGUAGAAAUUUGCAAAAUUCUAUUGUUUCCUACACAAGAAGUACCAAAAAACUACUAAGGAAUAUGAUGGAUGAGCAACAAGCUUCCUUGGAUUAUUUAUCUAAUCAGGUUAACGAGCUCAUGAAUAGAGUUCUCCUUUUGACUACAGAAGUUUUUAGAAAACAGCUGGAUCCUUUUCCUCACAGACCUGUUCAGUCACAUGGUUUAGAUUGCACUGAUAUUAAGGAUACCAUUGGCUCUGUCACCAAAACACCGAGUGGUUUAUACAUAAUUCACCCAGAAGGAUCUAGCUACCCAUUUGAGGUAAUGUGUGACAUGGAUUACAGAGGAGGUGGACGGACUGUGAUACAGAAAAGAAUUGAUGGGAUAAUUGAUUUCCAGAGGUUGUGGUGUGAUUAUCUGGAUGGAUUUGGAGAUCUUCUAGGAGAAUUUUGGCUAGGACUGAAAAAGAUUUUUUAUAUAGUAAAUCAGAAAAAUACCAGUUUUAUGCUGUAUGUGGCUUUGGAAUCUGAAGAUGACACUCUUGCUUAUGCAUCAUAUGAUAAUUUUUGGCUAGAGGAUGAAACGAGAUUUUUUAAAAUGCACUUAGGACGGUAUUCAGGAAAUGCUGGUGAUGCAUUCCGGGGUCUCAAAAAAGAAGAUAAUCAAAAUGCAAUGCCUUUUAGCACAUCAGAUGUUGAUAAUGAUGGGUGUCGCCCUGCAUGCCUGGUCAAUGGUCAGUCUGUGAAGAGCUGCAGUCACCUCCAUAACAAGACCGGCUGGUGGUUUAACGAGUGUGGUCUAGCAAAUCUAAAUGGCAUUCAUCACUUCUCUGGAAAAUUGCUUGCAACUGGAAUUCAAUGGGGCACGUGGACCAAAAACAACUCACCUGUCAAGAUUAAAUCUGUUUCAAUGAAAAUUAGAAGAAUGUACAAUCCAUAUUUUAAAUAAUCUCAUUUAACAUUGUAAUGCAAGUUCUACAAUGAUAAUAUAUUAAAGAUUUUUAAAAGUUUAUCUUUUCACUUAGUGUUUCAAACAUAUUAGGCAAAAUUUAACUGUAGAUGGCAUUUAGAUGUUAUGAGUUUAAUUAGAAAACUUCAAUUUUGUAGUAUUCUAUAAAAGAAAACAUGGCUUAUUGUAUGUUUUUACUUCUGACUAUAUUAACAAUAUACAAUGAAAUUUGUUUCAAGUGAACUACAACUUGUCUUCCUAAAAUUUAUAGUGAUUUUAAAGGAUUUUGCCUUUUCUUUGAAGCAUUUUUAAACCAUAAUAUGUUGUAAGGAAAAUUGAAGGGAAUAUUUUACUUAUUUUUAUACUUUAUAUGAUUAUAUAAUCUACAGAUAAUUUCUACUGAAGACAGUUACAAUAAAUAACUUUAUGCAGAUUAAUAUAUAAGCUACACAUGAUGUAAAAACCUUACUAUUUCUAGGUGAUGCCAUACCAUUUUAAAAGUAGUAAGAGUUUGCUGCCCAAAUAGUUUUUCUUGUUUUCAUAUCUAAUCAUGGUUAACUAUUUUGUUAUUGUUUGUAAUAAAUAUAUGUACUUUUAUAUCCUGA